GGAAACGCGCCGCGGGGCUGUUAGCUCGGCUGGGCACGGGCGGCUCCGUGGCGCUUCCUGCCACGCCAGGCCUGCCUGGGCCGCGCCAGCGCCGCUCCACCGAGGGCCGCGCGUCGGCCGCCGCCGGGCCUGGAUGGGGCCUUACCUGCCAGGCUGAUCCCUUGGAGUAGUUCUGAGGCAUGAUGAGUCAUCCGUGUGUGUCUCUUUUGGGCGUUCCUGUUUUAAAUCCUGCCUUGGUCCCUCACCUGGCACAAGGACAAGUGCUACUGGUGUCAGACCCAUCGCCCAACACUGAUCCUGCUAAGUACUCUGAAAGCACCUCCGCGACCCGACACCAGAUGAAGGGGGAAGAUGCCCAGCCACAGGAGAUGGCGUCCACAAGCUUCCCAAGGGCCAGUGGUCCCAGUCCUGAAUUCAGACAGCACGGGGACUCUGACGGGAAGAGAGGGAGCCCACAGAAUCUGCCCAUAGAACAUCAUUUUGCUUGUAAAGAGUGUGGGGACACCUUUCGGCUUAAAGUCCUGCUUGUCCAGCACCAGAGAGUCCACAGUGAGGAGAAGGGCUGGGAAUGUGGCGACUGCGGGAAGGUCUUUAGGGGGGUGGCGGAGUUUAAUGAGCACAGGAAAAGCCACGUAGCUGCGGAGCCCCAGCCCGGCCCCAGUAGGGCCCUGGAGAAUGCCGCGGAGAAGAGGGAGCAGAUGGAGAGGGAGGCAAAGCCCUUCGAGUGCGAGGAGUGCGGAAAACGGUUUAAGAAGAAUGCAGGCCUGAGUCAGCAUCUGAGGGUCCACAGCAGAGAGAAGCCCUUUGAUUGCGAGGAAUGCGGGCGGUCGUUCAAAGUCAACACCCACCUCUUCCGACAUCAGAAACUUCACACUUCGGAAAAGCCUUUCGCCUGCAAGGCGUGCAGCAGGGAUUUCCUGGAUCGCCAGGAGCUUCUCAAGCACCAGCGCAUGCACACUGGCCACCUGCCCUUCGACUGCGACGACUGCGGCAAGUCCUUCCGAGGGGUCAACGGGCUGGCCGAGCACCAGCGCAUCCACAGUGGGGCCAAGCCAUACGGGUGUCCCCACUGCGGCAAGCUCUUCCGAAGGAGCUCGGAGCUCACCAAGCACCGGCGGAUCCACACGGGCGAGAAGCCCUACGCCUGCGGCCAGUGCGGCAAGGCCUUCCGCCAGAGCUCCAGCCUCCUGGAGCACGCACGCAUCCACAGUGGCGAGCGGCCCUACGCAUGCGGCGAGUGUGGCAAGGCCUUCCGUGGGCCCUCUGACCUCAUCAAGCACCGGCGCAUCCACAGCGGACUGAAACCCUAUGAGUGCGACAAAUGCGGCAAGGCCUUCCGCCGGAGCUCCGGCCUCAGUCGCCACCGGCGGAUCCACAGUGGGGCGCGGCGCUGCGAAUGCAGCCAGUGUGGCCGCGUGUUCAAGAGGCGCUCGGCACUGCAGAAGCAUCAGCCAACCCACCACGAGUAGAAACGCCCUGUGGUCCCGCGGGACAGGGACGGAGUCCCCAGAGGGGAUGGCAGAGUCAAAGGAGAUGAACAGUUUUGUAGCGCUUAUAUAUUUUGUCUUCCAAAAGGUUGAGACCGAUUUAUACUGCCACCAGCAAUUUAUAAGUGUUACGUUAUGCCCAUCAAGAGUAGCUUGUACCAUUUAACUUAGUUUGGCUAGUUUAACUGGUAGGAAGUACCAUCAAGGUAUUUCAGUCCACAUGCCUUGAAUCCAAGAAUGAGAGAGGACAAAUCUGGAUGUGGGGUAGGGAGGGGCUUAGAGGUCAUCAACUCCAAGCUCCCCCCGCCCCAGAGAAACACACAGAGCUGUUCCACGAUGGCGUCCUCAUAAUGUGAUCCCAGCUUUCCUGAAGAGAACGUUGCCCUCAUGAUUUUUGGCCUACUUGAAUUUAUAAAUUUUUAGGGAUGUAAAUAGAACACUCAAAUGUCUUAAAAUAUUUAAUUUAUUAAUUUAGUUAUACAUACAUACUGUAAAUCACAUAUUAUAUAAAAUAAUAUAUUAAUUUAGAAAAUACCCCAUUUUUGCCACCCUCCCUUUCACGAAAUCAUUUUACUCUGACUCCUCACCGUCUUCACCAACAUGGGAACCCUGUUUGAGUCAUCAGACAGUUUCAAGACACACCCAGUCACUUCCAUCCGAGCUCUGCACGGUCGCUCAGUGACGAUCCCUUCAUGAGGCUCUCAUUAGAAAUUUUCUCCCAAGCCAUAAGACCAUAUUUGCAGAACAUUAGGACGAUUUCUCUUGUCGUUUUUUAAUCUGUCCUGUGACUGUACAAUAUAACCACUUAAGGUCAUACUUUUUCAAACAACCUUUAAACGUCUUUUCUUUUAAAGCACCCAAAAUGUCAUUGUGAGGCCAAACGCCUAGUAACAGUUACUGAAUCUGGGUUAAAUGUCGGUAUCUUUUUUUCUUAAACCAUUUCAAUUUGGUGUCCCCUAUACAUAUCCAAAACUAGCAUCGAUUGGGGUUGUUUUGAACUAAUGGGUCUUGUCCUCAAGCAGCACUAUUUUGUUCAAAAUAAAAUAGUUGAGAGCAUGCCCCUAAGAAGAGAUACAUCUCAAGGACUCAAGUGCAGGGUGACGCCUCCUUUUGGAAAUGAGCCUCUCCUGGUAUCAGGCCUAGAUGGUACUUCUCCAGCCUUCCGUUUCUUGUUCUAUAAAACAGGGGUGAUCACAGCACCUACCUCCGAAGGUUAUCACGAGGACUGCCAUCGUGGCUGCAGAGUGCCAGGACCACCGGCCUGGUAUGGAGGUACACACUCAGUGAAGGCCAUCUGCUGUCAUUGUCAUUGUCAUAGUUAUUGCCGUCAUUCUGUGGCUUGUCAAUUCCAGAACUGGGGAUAGACCCCAGGCCUCCUGACCACCAGUCUCAUCUUUCUCUUAUGCGAUGACUUAAAUGGUGUUUCUGUUUUUUGCAUGCAAAUGGUCCGUUCAUCUCCUUUGACUAGUUAUCAACUUACCUUCGGAUAUAUUAACUUUAUGUAGCAGUUCUUUCUAUAUUGAUGGUGAUGUUCUCUUUUCCAAUUUUAUUGCUUUGCUUUUUGUAGCAGUUUUAUUACGUUUUUGUUGUGAAAGCUUUUAAUUUUUACAUAUCCAAGCAUUCAUUUUUUGUCCACUCAGUCAUAACUUUCAUUGCUUCUGUAGCUAGAUAUGAUGACAUUUUCUCUAGAAUUUUAAUUACAAACAAAAAGCUGCAACCCCAGCCCAUCAGAAGGUGAGUACACCAGGUGGGCAGGCUGGAUGGAAAUGGGCCAGAGAAGCAGGCUCUUUCCUCAUCCGAGAUGCGGACUCCCUGUCUAUCUGUGGGCACCACUUGACUAUCCAACCUGACCACUGCGGCACACUGGAGAUGCUCCCAUCAUAGAUUAGCCAGAACUCUGUGACUGCUCAUCAUUAUAGACCCCGCCAGCAGCAGUGGGGCUUGGCCUCACCUAGAUCAAUGGAGUGGUCCAAACUUGGUCUGGGAGCAAGCAGCCCAGCCAUCCUUUGAGCUCCUGGGAGCCUUGGCAAUGCUCCGAGUGGAUUCAGUGACUGAGCAGCAGAUUCACCCAAGAAACAUCUCCUUGGACACAAGAAGACUUGCCUAGACCACAUCCUCCUUUCAGCCGGUGACUCUAGAACUAGAAAGAGAUUGGUUCAUAGGCUUCUGCUGUGGGCAGCUAGGGGAAAAUUCACCCAUGUGUUCUGGCAUCACUUCCUAUAGCCACACCUAAGUGAGGGCAACAGAGCAGAGGCUCGGAGAGGAACCCUGCCCCUCCGAUGGCUUGUGCGUUAUGCUGAUAGAAGCUGGCAGCACUGCCCUGGGCUAUGAUUUGCAACAGCCAUGCCCAGGAGGAGCACUAAAGCAAAGGUUUGGAGGGCAGUGGAACCCUUCUGAAAGCCUGUGUGGCAUAGAAGUAGAAGCUGGUCCUCCUGGGUCUGAGCUACCAUUUCCAGUGGGCUCCCCCAAGAGGAACAGCAGCAAGGGCUAGCGAGGAACCUGCCCCUCCAGUGGCCCACAGAAGCCACAGAUAGAAGCCAGCCCCACCAGGGCUGUGCUGUGACUUCCCAGCAGCUGUGGCUGGGGACAGGGACACUAGGAGGGCCUGGCAAGGAAGUGUGCCCUUCUCGUGGGCCCACCAAGGCUGAGGCAGAGCUUCCUAGCAGACACAACUUGGAAGGGCUUCUCAGGCACCCAUCCUGACCCCCAGGCUGGAGAGGAGCCAAAAGCACUUGUUACAUAGUGAUUCCUUUUGCCCUGUGGGCCUCAGUUCUUGCAGUAGUUGUGAAUCUGUGUCUGAAAUCACUACUUUCUUCUCGGAUCCUUUUUCUCUUUUCGAGUUGUUAGGAUGUGUUUUGUACAGCUGUCAUUUGAUAAAGAAGGUUGACCUCUACCAGGGGCAAGUCUGGCACCUUUACCUAGAAGUACUCUGCCAUGUCUUGCCCGUUCAUUUAUCGUUUGUUGGGUUUCAUGAGGGAUCCCAUUGAAGUAGAUCCCUUUUAUGAAGGGAUCCCAUUGAAUGCAGCAUUAACUCAGAACGUAGCAUAAAGUCGUCACUGCUCCCAGCUGGGACGUGGUGUCUUGGCAUCCCUUCCUGCCGUCCUUGACUCUUUCCCAUCUUCAGUUCUAUAAUUUUCUCCCAAACAAAUGCUCUUUUAGAGUUAACACUAAAGAUCUGGUCUUUGCCGUCAAGGUUGACAGAACAGCUGUUCAUGGUGUUUGCGGUGAAACCCGUGUUCUCUUUCAAUGCAGUCUGUGGCUUUAACGUGUGUCCUGUAAUUUCGCCAAGAUCAUUUCUUGCCUCUGGUAACUUGGGGGUGGAUUUCCUUGGGCUCUCUAGGUGUACUGCUAUGUCAGAUGCAAAAUGUCACCCAGCUUCCUGUCACAUAUCCUUGUCUGUGCAUUCAUGCAUCUACCUCAUUCCGGUUUUCUUUCUAAUCUCAUGUAUUCCUGUUGUGAGGAAAUGUGUUCUUUUCCCGAUCCUUUUGUAGUUCAUACACAUGACAAUUGGGUUUCCACGCACGUGCAUGAGAUGUUCCUCCUUCAAACCUUGUUACUAUGUCAGCACAUUAACUGCCUGGCAUGGAAAAAGAAAAAAAAAAAAGAAAUAUGUUCUUUUCCUACCAUUUGAAAAAAAUCCUCCAUUGCUUUUAUUAGAGUUUUGAAUACUUGUGAAAAUUUUCAAAAGAAAGUAAUUGAUUACCAUUUUUGCUGCUUAUUACGAUGAGCUGUGUCCAUUAGCUGUGUCACCCCACUCUUGCAUUUCCAGAAUAGUCCCUACCCAAUUGCAGCGGGCAUGUUUUUGAGUGGUGUUGCAUUCCAUGUGCUUGAUUUUGUCCUAGAACUGGCACAGCGCCUGCCCUACCUGCAGCCCUGGGUUGUGGCCCUGUUGCGUACCAUGUGAUUUGCCACCCCGCUUCUAGGCCAUAUUAAUUCAGCCAGAACUGAACACCUGACCCAAGGGCAGCAAGCAAUCAUCAGAGCAUAGAGCUGACAGAACAUGAUGGACCACGGACACCACCAGGCCUUCCAGAUCUGAAAUGCAAACAAGGAAACAGAAGCUUCUAGGCAUCAGAAGGUGUGGGGAGCAGCACAGUACUCAGAGGAGUGAGGAGCGUGGCGCCUGCUGGGAGGAAGGCCUGGCCAUGGUAUGUUCUUGGAUUUCUGGCAGCAGCCCUCAUUGGUCCACGUGCGUCCCCACUACAGACUCCUUGACUUGAGCCAGCUUGAGUGGGUCUCUACUCUUUUCUAUUGUGUUUUGCCACUUGGCUGCUUCCUGGCCAAGUCGCACCUGACUGCAUGAACACCUGUUCAAACGUGUGUUCUCUGUUCUCUAAGAUGGGUGAAAGUCGAUGCCUUCUAGUCUCAGUGAAUUUAACCUGUGAUUUUAUGUCUACGUAUAUUGUUCCUUUACUGAACCCACCACAUGCGGGCCAUAAAAUGAGUGAAAUCACAGUGCACCCUGUUCUCUUAUUUUUGAAGUGUUUCACGAUUUCCAGCAUGUCCAUCAGAUGGGGGGAUUGCUAACUUCUCUCUUACUCAUGUACUUACAUUCUGUAGUUCUCAUUGCAUCACUUUGGAUGUUUACUUUGAAAAGCAGAAACUGUCUCUUUAAACUUGGCCCUCAAUGUCAUUUGCGUAUCUCUGAGAACAAUAGCUAUGUCCCACCCCAGUUUGUAUUUCCGUUGGUUGUUGGCACUUUUUUCUCAUUCCCCCAUCUCAUUACCUUGUCUGUUUUCUGGCACUCACUAUAAUCAGCCUUGCACUAGAGCUGUUUGUGGACUUGGCUUCACCCCCUCCUCCUCAGCCCUCCCCCACCCAUUAAAUUGUGAGCUCUUAGAAGACAGGGGUGGCCUUUCAUGUCUGAUCCCCUACCAAAUCUAGCACAGUGCCUUGCAUCAAGUAGAUUUCAAUAAAUAUAUGUUAAAUGGCA